AGUGUUGAGCAUCUGUCCCCCUUUAGAUCUCUGAAGCCACAAAUAGGAUGCUUGGGAAGACUCCUAGCUGUCCUUUUUCCUCUCCACACAGUGCUCAAGGCCAGCUUAUAGUCAUAUAUAUCACCCAGACAUAAAGGAAAAGACACAUUUUUUAGGAAAUGUUUUUAAUAAAAGAAAAUUACAAAAAAAAAUUUUAAAGACCCCUAACCCUUUGUGUGCUCUCCAUUCUGCUCCUUCCCCAUCGUUGCCCCCAUUUCUGAGGUGCACUGGGAGGCUCCCCUUCUAUUUGGGGCUUGAUGACUUUCUUUUUGUAGCUGGGGCUUUGAUGUUCCUUCCAGUGUCAUUUCUCAUCCACAUACCCUGACCUGGCCCCCUCAGUGUUGUCACCAGAUCUGAUUUGUAACCCACUGAGAGGACAGAGAGAAAUAAGUGCCCUCUCCCACCCUCUUCCUACUGGUCUCUCUAUGCCUCUCUACAGUCUCGUCUCUUUUACCCUGGCCCCUCUCCCUUGGGCUCUGAUGAAAAAUUGCUGACUGUAGCUUUGGAAGUUUAGCUCUGAGAACCGUAGAUGAUUUCAGUUCUAGGAAAAUAAAACCCGUUGAUUACUAUAUUGGAUUCUGACUGAUUCUUUGGGGGUGUAUUGGUUAACUGAAGACAGAAAGUGGGGUAAUGGAAUGCAAAUGAUUUCCAGGUCAUCUCAGAUUUAGGUAGAGGGUGUCAACCUCCUCCAUUUUUAGGCAUUUGGAAAUCCAAACUUCUUGUGGGCAGAGUCGUAGAAUAAACCACACCAUUCAUUCUACUCCUGCCCAGCCACUGUUUAACGCACCUGGGAAAGUUUUUUUUAAAAAAGGGUUUGCACAAGAAGUGGGGUGUGGGAGGAUGCGAGUAUCGGCCACAGCCCAAGAUGGCCAUGAAGUGGGAGUUUGGAGGCUGGUUGUAUAAACAAUUUGACCCCAAAGUGCAAGUCAAAUAAUAGGAUAACCCUUUCUCCUUGCUAAUGCUAGGGGUACCUGCCACCCUUAGCUGGUGAUGGGGUGGUAGGGGGAGGGGGUUGGUAGGGUGAAAUUCCGCCAGUACUCCCUGAGUUAAGUGGAAUGACUGGUUUAGAUCAUUUCUGUUUCCUUCCAGAUCUGACAUUUUGUAACUAGAUCGGCUACUAGCAUUGGAAGGGCCCACGUUUCAUCCCUUCCUCUAGAAAGCCUACCGGCAGUUUUUGAAUCUGCCCUGCCCCCACUCCAGCAGAGAAGGACAGGGAGAGCAUUGGCGGUAGCCCUGUCUGGAAAGGGCGGCCCUUUGCCUUGAACAGGAAGCCACAACCACCUAGAAAAUGGAGCCUUCUUCUCUAGAAACUACAAUUCCCAGCGGCCUCCACGCAGAGCAUGCGCGGGAAUGUGCCAGGCGGGCCAGCCGAACCAGCUUGCCUUUCGAUUCCCGACAUGCUUCAUGGUGUGUUCCGGUUUCCUUGAUUUCCUACCCCCGCCAAACUUCCUGUUUCCAGCUUUCUAGCGGCGGACUACAACUCCCAGCAUGCUGAGAGAGCUGACAAGGAAGGUUUCGAGCGUUUUGCUGGCAAAGGGAUUUCUUACAACCUCCAGGCAUGCGUCUUUCUGCCCUGCUGGCCUUGGCAUCCAAGGUCACUCUGCCCCCCCAUUACCGCUAUGGGAUGAGCCCCCCAGGCUCUGUUGCAGACAAGAGGAAGAACCCCCCAUGGAUCAGGCGGCGCCCAGUGGUUGUGGAACCCAUCUCUGAUGAAGACUGGUAUCUGUUCUGUGGGGACACGGUGGAGAUCCUAGAAGGCAAGGAUGCCGGGAAGCAGGGCAAAGUGGUUCAAGUUAUCCGGCAGCGAAACUGGGUGGUCGUGGGAGGGCUGAACACACAUUACCGCUACAUUGGCAAGACCAUGGAUUACCGGGGAACCAUGAUCCCUAGUGAAGCCCCCUUGCUCCACCGCCAGGUCAAACUUGUGGAUCCUAUGGACAGGAAACCCACUGAGAUCGAGUGGAGAUUUACUGAAGCAGGAGAGCGGGUACGAGUCUCCACACGAUCAGGGAGAAUUAUCCCUAAACCCGAAUUUCCCAGAGCUGAUGGCAUCGUCCCUGAAACGUGGAUUGAUGGCCCCAAAGACACAUCAGUGGAAGAUGCUUUAGAAAGAACCUAUGUGCCCUGUCUAAAGACACUGCAGGAGGAGGUGAUGGAGGCCAUGGGGAUCAAGGAGACCCGGAAAUACAAGAAGGUCUAUUGGUAUUGAGCCUGGGGCAGAGCAGCUCCUCCCCAACUUCUGUCCCAGCCUUGAAGGCUGAGGCACUUCUUUUUCAGAUGCCAAUAAAGAGCACUUUAUGAGUC